AGCAUUUGUCAGAGUGAUUUGACUCUGGCUGGUCACCAGGUAAUCUGUCCAAAGUUCAGAAGGUGUCAGGAUGCUAUCCUGAGGCUCCACAGUGACAGCCUCUCAGUCUGUGCACUGUCCCCCACGGGUGGCCCCAAAGCCAGCUGCCCAUUUAACUGGGCACAGCAUGGACACUGGCCUCAGCUCUCAGCCUUCUGAGGAGGACCAGUCCACCAUGCCUGAAGUCAAAGACCUCUCAGAAGCCUUGCCAGAAACGUCAAUGGAUCCCAUCACGGGAGUCGGGGUGGUGGCUUCUCGGAACCGAGCCCCGACAGGCUAUGACGUAGUUGCACAGACAGCAGAUGGUGUGGAUGCUGACCUCUGGAAAGACGGCUUAUUUAAAUCCAAGGUUACCAGAUACCUGUGUUUCACAAGAUCAUUUUCCAAAGAAAAUAGUCAUCUGGGGAACGUGUUAGUAGAUAUGAAGCUCAUUGACAUCAAGGACACACUGCCUGUGGGCUUCAUCCCAAUUCAGGAGACGGUGGACACACAGGAAGUGGCUUUUAGGAAGAAGAGGCUGUGCAUUAAAUUUAUUCCACGGGAUUCAACGGAAGCUGCGAUUUGUGACAUUCGGAUCAUGGGCCGGACCAAGCAGGCCCCGCCUCAGUACACGUUUAUUGGGGAACUGAACAGCAUGGGGAUCUGGUAUCGAAUGGGCAGAGUACCAAGAAAUCAUGACUCAUCUCAACCCACAACGCCUUCCCAGUCAUCAGCUGCCUCCACCCCAGCCCCCAACCUUCCCAGGCACAUCUCCCUAACACUUCCUGCCACCUUCCGAGGCAGGAACAGCACCCGGACGGACUACGAGUACCAGCACUCCAAUUUGUAUGCCAUAUCAGCAAUGGAUGGUGUGCCUUUUAUGAUUUCAGAGAAGUUUUCUUGUGUUCCAGAAAGUAUGCAGCCCUUUGAUCUCCUGGGAAUCACCAUCAAAUCUCUAGCAGAAAUCGAAAAAGAGUACGAGUACAGCUUCCGCACAGAGCAGAGCGCAGCCGCCAGGCUCCCGCCCAGCCCCACCAGGUGUCAGCAGAUCCCGCAGUCCUGAGGAGCCAGCGGCCACCUGCGGGGAGACCACCGCCGCCCAGACUACUGACGGCAGGGGCUGCUGCCCCCGCCUCCUCCUGCCGCCUCCGCCAGCCCUCCCUCCCACACUGCCCCAGCAGGGCUGGCCCGGAGACUGGGCAGCUAAGUGGGCGCAUCCUGUCUUCAGCUGGCCUCACUGACACCCCGGCCUCCCUGGGGACAUUGUUCAUAACCAUGACUAAUCUGUGUGUGCUGUAGUGACCAGCGGCUCCUAACGUGUCUGUGUGAUGACCAGUUGUCCUCCAAAAACCUCACUCACCACGGAGUCACCCUGAGGGCCCCGGGCAGUUGCCCUGGCCGCCCAGUGACGCCCACCGGCUCCCUCCGCUCCCUCCUGUCACCUACCAGGGCAGACCCCACUAAGCCGUUGAGUCUCUUCCUGGAAGACCCUGAGGGCCGGCAGCUUUGCCUAGGACUCUCCAGGGUCGCUGAUCCUCCCCGGCCCAGGGCUGCCAGGAACAAGUUCCUCUCUGCAGGAUCUCACAGCAGCCCUGAGAAGACAUGGGAGGAAGAAGCCAGUGGCCCUGGGGUGGACCCUGCCCUUUGGACAUCCCAUGGACUUGUCACCCAGUCGCCUGGAAGUCGGGGAGCAGCACCCCUGCCCCCGGUGGAGGGGUUGUUGCUUUCUGGGGAGGAGGACGGUUGACGGCCCUGCUUGGAUCCACCACCAGGACGCUGUGCUCGGCCAUGGCGCGCCUCCCCCAAGGGCUCAUCUGUGCAACAACCACAUGCCAACAAUAGCUCCAGGUGCCUCAGCCCCGUGCCCUGACCCGGGGACCACAGGGACACCCUCUGAGACGUGCUGGCCCCAGGAGGAUACAGGCACACGGGCACCCAGCCCCUCUCAGAGCCAGGCGUGUCUUGACGGUAUCUGCUGACGGGAACAAGUCAUUCUGAAAGGUCCCUCUGACCCAGGUCACCAAAUUUGGGCCAGAACUGGCACUUCCGAGUGCCCACUGGUGCUGGCGUCCUCAAAGUGCCGGGCGCCAAGUUCAGCCCCAGGUGCGUUUGCCUAGGCAGUGGUGGCUGCCAUCCCUCGGGGCCCAGGCCCUCACCCGAAGGGCUGCCUCACUCUGUGGUGUCAGGCACUGGGCUGUGUCCUGAUUCCUCAGAGUAUGGGGACCUGACAUCUUUGGGUCCCCAAGAGUUGGCUCUUGGAUGUGGAGGCUUGAUGCUGCGGUUGGGGGCUGCACUACCUGCGUCCGUGGAAGCCUCUGCCUCAGCGGGGACGGCCUCCUGCUGCAGGUCCUGGGCAGCCCACAGUAGUGCUAGCUGAGGCCCAGAGGAACGGGAGGAAAGGGAGGCAGCGCCGGACGGCGCAGCUGGCCAAGAGGCGGGCGGGGCCAGAAAUACCUCAUGCCCCUGCACCAGCCCCUCCGUCUCCAGGCCCCAGGCCUCUUUGUGGACCCAUCUUCCUCCUCUGCCACCCCGAUCUUCACUCGGAUACCUCUUGAUUUCUGUGGAUAAGGGAAGCGGCCACUUCUCCCUCCCUGAGACCCGAGGAUGCCCCUGGUGGGGGUGGCCUUCUCAGGACUCCUGGGUGGCACAGCAGCAGGACCUUGUCAUGGGACUGAUGCUGAGCAGGGAGGGGGCUGCCAGGCUGGCUGCCGAUGCUCCGUUCACAUAAGCCAGUGUGGUUCUGGGGACCUGAGGAGCCCUGUGGCACCCACAGGGGGCACCUAUGUCUGCCGUGGCUCCUCGGGUGGUGCCCUGUGUGACAAAGCCCAACAGCAAGGGUGACUCCUGGCAGGUGGGGGCAGCAGGAGGGCAGAGGGCAGAGCUCUGGCCACUUCUGCCCACUUCAUUAGGGUUUGUGAACUUUGUCCUUCACCUCUUUUCGUGCCCUGGUUGUGAGAUUGCCUCUAACAGGUAAUGCCAGGGGCCCUUCACUCCGCCCCCAUGACUGGGAAGAGGCCUGUGGCAGCGCCGCUGGACCCUAGGAGGCUCAGAGGCAGUGGUGUGGGAGCCCUGUCUGCAAGGACGCAGAAUAAGCAGUGAGGGCGGCUGCAGGAGAGGAAGGGGCUCCCACAGCCCCCACUGAUGCCGCUGCAGGCCCCUGUCGAGCUGGGGUCCCAGCCAGGUGCCCCCGCAUGCCCUCCUGCAGUUGCUGGAUGGAUAGGGACACCAGGAAGAGGACAAACUGCAUGGACUCAAGCGAGCUGGAGCCAUCUUCUCCAUAGCAUUACGGACUUAGCAUAAGAGUAAAUGACUGUGAACGUUGUAGUAAACGGCAGCUUAAGAUAAGUAAGCAGAGACAGUGUUAAGGACGAGUUGGUGUCUGUGGUAGCUUUUAGGCUGCUCCUAACCCACCAUUUAUUGCCUUCUGAGAGGUGGGUGAGGACAAGCAUGUGCCUGUGUGUGUGUGUGUGUGUGUGUGUAUAUGUGUGUGUGUGCACGCACAUGCGUGUGUAUAAGCCCACCUGAGUGGGGCUCGUGCAGGAGAACUGAGGCAUGAAACUCUGGCUCAAACCUAGGAAUUGAGAGCGUUUCUGUCUUUUGGGAGAGUACUUUUCUCCACGAGCCCUCUGGCCACUGUGGGAGGGAAGGACAAGGGUUCCCUUGGAAAUGUGAAGGGUCUUGGCCUCAUCCCUCAGGUCCCCCCACAGCACUUCCCACUACUGCUUCUGUCCCUGCUGGCAGCCUCUGUCCCUCCAGAACGGCUAACCAGAGCACACUGUCCCCACCGCCUCCCCUUUCUCUCUGGAAAGUUGAAGUAUCUCCAAAGGCCUUGGAAAUGGCACAAAGGUGAUAAGGAGCAGGUGCUUUGCUGCAGUCUCCCUUGCAAAUGUAUAAUUAAGGCCUUUCUUCCCACCCCAAGUCCAAGAACAAAUGCCAGCCACGUCCUCCGCCACUUGGAGAGAUGAGAACCCAGUGGGGUCACGUAAAGGAAUUGCAGGUCGGUGAGAGGACAAGAGGGACUCCCAUGUUCUAAGCACCUGUUCCUGGCCAGGCUCUAGGCCAGGCUCUCUAAGCACAUUUCUCCUUUCAUUCCCCCUAAAAACAGAGUGACCUGGAAGUAGAUGUUCUUUGCUCCUUGUCAGAGUUGAAGAGGCUGACUUGGCCCACUGCUAAGCGGCAGAGGCAGGGCCAGCCAUCCUGUCGCAAGCCCGUGCUGGGGCUGCCCUUUCUGUUUCCAGUCCAGUUACGGACUUCCCGGCCGCCACUGGGCCCUGCCGGUCACCAGGCCACUGUGCAGUGGGCGCAGAGCAUGGUCAGGAGUGGCCUGCCCGUACUCCUCCACCCAGAUGAGGGCCCUCCAGAGCCUGCAGGCAUCUGUGGGGAAUCCCAGCCUGCAGGUUCUUGGAGAAGCAGGUGAACCUAAGGAUGAAAGCAAAGGAGGGCCUUGAGGAAGCAGCCCCCAGGCCUGGCAGCCACGCAGCGGCUGAGCUCAUGAACUUGGUUCGCAGCCUGCCUUGCCCCUGGAGGCCACGCCAGGCGCUCACCCCUGAGCCCACAGCCCCUGCUUGGGCUGCCUGGCACCCUCAGGGUGGCCCGGCCUCCUCCUGCCACUCUGAGCACAUGUCCGGGGGUUGCCACCAGAGACGGCUUUGUUCUCCCAGCUAAGGCCGUGGAGCUGCUGUGUGACUGUGUCAGGCCUGGACAAGGAAGACCCUUAGGGAUGACGUCCCCGCUGCAUAUUUAUUCAAGGUGACUCUUGUACUUGGCAAGGGAAGUCCACUGUGUGAUUGUCUGUAUUCUUAAUAUAAUUUGUUAAAUAAACGUUUGUUUUAACCUCUUU